CUGCAGGCGCGCCCUGGCACCCGGGCCAAGACGCCCGGAGCGGCUGCUGCAGCCAGUAGCGGCCCCUUCACCGGCUGCCCCGCUCAGACCUAGUCGGGAGGGGUGCGAGGCAUGCAGCUGGGGGCCCAGCUCCGGUGCCGCACCCCGUAAAGGGCUGAUCUUCCACCUCGCCACCUCAGCCACGGGACGCCAAGACCGCAUCCAAUUCAGACUUCUUUUGGGUAAAGGGCCAAGAGGGAAGGGCGAGGCGGGGAGGAAGCAGCUCGGGCCGCCUUCCCUCCGUGGCCUCCAGGACAUCCGCCGGGGAUAGAUUAUGCGUUUCCAUUGGUUACCCACCUUGAGCGAGCCGUUUGAUAGAAACCAAGAGCUUGAAACGUGCAUUAGGCCAUUGUGGACUCCCAGUGGGAGUGCUUGUGAAACUGAACACAACAAAAGUAUGGAUAUGGGAAACCAACAUCCUUCUAUUAGUAGGCUUCAGGAAAUCCAAAAGGAAGUAAAAAGUGUAGAACAGCAAGUUAUCGGCUUCAGUGGUCUGUCAGAUGACAAGAAUUACAAGAAACUGGAGAGGAUUCUAACAAAACAGCUUUUUGAAAUAGACUCUGUAGAUACUGAAGGAAAAGGAGAUAUUCAGCAAGCUAGGAAGCGGGCAGCACAGGAGACAGAACGUCUUCUCAAAGAGUUGGAGCAGAAUGCAAACCACCCACACCGGAUUGAAAUACAGAACAUUUUUGAGGAAGCCCAGUCCCUCGUGAGAGAGAAAAUUGUGCCAUUUUAUAAUGGAGGCAACUGCGUAACUGAUGAGUUUGAAGAAGGCAUCCAAGAUAUCAUUCUGAGGCUGACACAUGUUAAAACUGGAGGAAAAAUCUCCUUGCGGAAAGCAAGGUAUCACACUUUAACCAAAAUCUGUGCGGUGCAAGAGAUAAUCGAAGACUGCAUGAAAAAGCAGCCUUCCCUGCCGCUUUCCGAGGAUGCACAUCCUUCCGUUGCCAAAAUCAACUUCGUGAUGUGUGAGGUGAACAAGGCCCGAGGGGUCCUGAUUGCACUUCUGAUGGGUGUGAACAACAAUGAGACCUGCAGGCACUUAUCCUGUGUGCUCUCGGGGCUGAUCGCUGACCUGGAUGCUCUAGAUGUGUGCGGCCGGACAGAAAUCAGAAAUUAUCGGAGGGAGGUAGUAGAAGAUAUCAACAAAUUAUUGAAAUAUCUGGAUUUGGAAGAGGAAGCAGACACAACUAAAGCAUUUGACCUGAGACAGAAUCAUUCCAUUUUAAAAAUAGAAAAGGUCCUCAAGAGAAUGAGAGAAAUAAAAAAUGAACUUCUCCAAGCACAAAACCCUUCUGAAUUGUACCUGAGCUCCAAAACAGAAUUGCAGGGUUUAAUUGGACAGUUGGAUGAGGUAAGUCUUGAAAAAAACCCCUGCAUCCGGGAAGCCAGGAGAAGAGCAGUGAUCGAGGUGCAAACUCUGAUCACAUAUAUUGACUUGAAGGAGGCCCUUGAGAAAAGAAAGCUGUUUGCUUGUGAGGAGCACCCAUCCCAUAAAGCCGUCUGGAACGUCCUUGGAAACUUGUCUGAGAUCCAGGGAGAAGUUCUUUCAUUUGAUGGAAAUCGAACCGAUAAGAACUACAUCCGGCUGGAAGAGCUGCUCACCAAGCAGCUGCUAGCCCUGGAUGCUGUUGAUCCGCAGGGAGAAGAGAAGUGUAAGGCUGCCAGGAAACAAGCUGUGAGGCUUGCGCAGAAUAUUCUCAGCUAUCUCGACCUGAAAUCUGAUGAAUGGGAGUACUGAAAUACCAGAGAUCUCACUUUUGAUACUGUUUUGCACUUCAUAUGUGCUUCUAUGUAUAGAGAGCUUUCAGUUCAUUGAUUUAUACGUGCAUAUUUCAGUCUCAGUAUUUAUGAUUGAAGCAAAUUCUAUUCAGUAUCUGCUGCUUUUGAUGUUGCAAGACAAAUAUCAUUACAGCACGUUAACUUUUCCAUUCGGAUCAUUAUCUGUAUGAUGUGGUGUGGUUUGUUUGGUUUGUCCUUUUUUUUGCGUUUUUAAUCAGAAAACAAAAUAGAGGCAGCUUUUGUAGAUUUUAAAUGGGUUGUGCAAGCAUUAAAAUGCAGGUCUUUCAGAAUCUAGAACUAGGCAUAACCUUACAUAAUACUAGGAAAAUUAUGAGAAAGGGGAAAUUUUUGGUUAAAUAAGAGUAAGGUUCAAACACAAGCAGUACAUGUUCUGUUUCAUUAUGCUCGAUAGAAGGCUUUUUUUUCACUUAUAAGGCCUGAUUGGUCCUACCCAGCUUAACGGGGUGGGGUUUUUUUGUUUGUUCAGACAGUCUGUUCUUUUGUAAACAUUUUUAGUUGGAAAAACAGCAUCUGCAUUUUCCCCAUCCUCUACGUUUUAGAGAGGAAUCUUGUUUUUGUGUGCAACAUAAGAAAAUUAUGAAAACUAAUAGCCAAAAAACCUUUGAGAUUGCAUUAAAGAGAAGGGAUAAAGGACCAGCAAUAAUACCUUGUAAGUUGCUUUUGUUUGUAAAAUCUGAGCUUAUAGUUUUCCUUAGUGAGUAAAUUCAUAAGGAUGGGAACAUUUAAAUUAAGUUAAUGGGCCUUUAAAAAAAAAAAAAGGAAACACUCAUACCUGUAGUUGGAGGAUGAAUACUGGAGACGGGUUACCAAUGUCAGGUUAUACUAAAACUAAAUCAGAAAGUCUGAAUGUAGCACAUAAUGGUUCUCUUCUGUUGUCCAAGGCUGUAAAAUGGACAGCCUUGUCACACCUCCCCGGUGCUGUUUUACAACGUGAGGGUAGACGCUGUCAGUAACCCAGAGGGACCAGGCCUUCCUAGGUUUUCUAGGCAGUCAGCUGUUAACCACUCACUUAGUAAAUGUCAUAACUACACCUGCUCCAGGACCAAUCAGUGAAACCUGCUCGGAAUUAAAGGCUUCCUCUGGGUGCCUGCUGAACAACUGAGCUCAUGUCAUGGGCAUGUGGUGGUUUCUCUGUUGCCUGAAAGAGCCAUUAAAGUCAGUCGUGCGUGAAGCAUCUCUCUUCUAAAGGAUGUGUAUUUCCAUAAAUGCUUUCUGAGGAUCCGGUACAAAAUGAUUUCCCAAAGUUCUGAAGUGCCUUGAGAACAUGUGGGUCCGAGUGUUAUAACAGACUCCUCCCCCGGGUCACCUUUUGCCUGGUCAUCCUGUUAGAGUACAUCUUUGGAAAUCCAGGGUAAUAUUCUCUUUCAGAGAUGCUCAUUGUGUAACUCUGUGUAGGGAGAUAGUCACUUUAAACAGCUCAAAGUAGCUAGCUAAAGGAGUAGCCUUAAAUACCUAAAAGAUGACAGAAGCAUAGCCCUUAACAAAUCUUCAGCUUGUCUCUCAGUAUUUCCCAAUCAUGAAAAUCCCUUGCUAUGUCUUUCCUACUAGAAAUGUUCUAGAAUCGCUGGACGGUGGGGUCAGAGGGCAGUCGGUAUUUAGGCCGUGAGCUUCCCAUACUACUGCAGGUCCAACUCCUGGCAACCGCGGGCUCAAGGCAGGUCAUUGGAAUCCACGUUUUGGCCACAGUAGUUGUAGGAUUGCUUUUCUGUAUCAUAAUUUUAGAAUGCUCUUAAAAUCUUGAGGAAGAGUUUUUAUUUUUUAUUUAUUUUUGAGAUGGAGUCUCUGUUGCCCAGGCUGCAGUGCAGUGGUGCCAUCUCAGCUCACUGCAACCUCCACCUCCCAGGUUCAAGCGAUUCUCCUGCCUCAGCCACCUGAGUAGCUGGGAGUACAGGCAUGUGGCACCAUGCCUGGCUAAUUUUUGUAUUUUUAAUAGAGUUGAGAUUUCACCAUGAUGGUCAGGCUGGUCUCGAACUCCUGACCUCGUGAUCCGCCCGCCUCGGCCCCCCAAAGUGCUGGGAUUAACGGGUGUGAGCCACGGCGCCCAGCCCAGGAAGAGUUUUUAAAUUAGAGCUCUGUUUAAUUAUACCACUGGGAAAUCAUGGUUACGCUUCAGGCAUAUUCUUCCCCAGAGUACUACUUACAUUUUAAAUUUCAUUUUGUAAAGUUAAAUGUCAGCAUUCCCUUUAAAAGUGUCCAUUGUUCUUUGAAAGUAGACGUUUCAGUCAUUCUUUUCAAACAAGUGUUUGUGUACCUUUUGCCAAGCUGUGGGCAUCGUGUGUGAGUACAGGGUGCUCAGCUCUUCCACCGUCAUUUUGAAUUGUUCACAUGGGUAAUUGGUCAUGGAAAUGAUCAGAUUGACCUUGAUUGACUGUCAGGCAUGGCUUUGUUUCUGGUUUCAAUCUGUUCUCGUUCCUUGUACCGGAUUAUUCUACUCCUGCAAUGAACCCUGUUGACACCGGAUUUAGCUCUUGUCGGCCUUCGUGGGGAGCUGUUUGUGUUAAUAUGAGCUACUGCAUGUAAUUCUUAAACUGGGCUUGUCACAUUGUAUUGUAUUUUUGUGAUCUGUAAUGAAAAGAAUCUGUACUGCAAGUAAAACCUACUCCCCAAAAAUGUGUGGCUUUGGGUCUGCAUUAAACGCUGUAGUCCAUGUUCAUGCCAAAAAUGGCUGGGAACGUUUGCUUUAUUUACAUUCAGUCAGCGUUGCUUUCAGAUCACACUUUAUCCACACAGGAAAGCCAGUCAGCCUAUAAUGAAGUAGUUAUUAAAAUAAAUGUAAUGAAUAUGUCUACAAAGUAUAGUUUAGUGGUUUAUUUUGCUAAAAUGCACAUAUAUUUGAUAUAAUUUAGUUUGAGAAGUUCAGCUAGUUUUUCUCCUUUGUUUGACUUUGUCAAUUUCUAUCUGGUUUUUAAGGGUCUGAGCUUAGCUUGUGCAUGCAAGGUUUUGGGUUUUUUUAUUUUUUUUUUGAGCACAGCUUUUCACCUUUUAAUUUGUUGGGUAUUUUUCUCUUAAUAAGAGAAAUAUUGGCCAUCGAUUUUUACAUAUAAUACAAGUGUGUUUUUCCAGUACAUUGGUUCCUGUCCCCUCUCUGUGAACUGUUUGAGUAUUGGAACAGUAUGUCUUCAAUAAUUCAAUGUUACUUUGAGAUACAUGUGUUAAUAUACCCUUAGUUAUUCUUGAAAUAAAACCAGUCUCUUACGCUUGCAGUGGA